AGGUGCUGGAGGUGCUGUCAUGGCCUGCCUCAACCCGGUGCCUAAACUCUACAGAUCUGUAAUUGAAGAUGUAAUUGAAGGAGUUCGGAAUCUAUUUGCUGAAGAAGGUAUAGAGGAACAAGUUUUAAAAGACUUGAAGCAGCUCUGGGAAACCAAGGUUUUGCAGUCUAAAGCAACAGAAGACUUCUUCAGAAAUAGCAUCCAAUCACCUCUGUUUACUCUUCAGUUGCCGCACAGCUUGCACCAAACAUUGCAAUCGUCAACAGCAUCAUUAGUUAUUCCUGCUGGUAGAACUCUUCCAAGUUUUACCACAGCAGAACUGGGCACUUCAAACUCCAGUGCAAACUUUACUUUUCCUGGUUAUCCCAUUCAUGUACCAGCAGGUGUGACACUACAGACUGUAUCUGGUCACCUUUAUAAAGUCAAUGUACCAAUUAUGGUGACAGAGACUUCUGGAAGAGCAGGUAUUCUUCAGCAUCCAAUUCAGCAAGUAUUUCAACAGCUUGGCCAGCCUUCAGUAAUACAAACUAGUGUUCCACAAUUGAAUCCAUGGUCUCUUCAAGCAACUACUGAAAAAUCACAGAGAAUUGAAACCGUGCUACAGCAACCCGCAAUUCUACCUUCUGGGCCAGUAGAUAGGAAACACUUAGAAAAUGCCACCAGUGAUAUACUUGUAUCUCCUGGAAAUGAGCAUAAAAUCGUGCCUGAAGCUUUGUUGUGUCAUCAGGAAAGUUCUCACUAUAUCAGUCUUCCAGGUGUUGUAUUUUCUCCACAGGUCUCUCAAACAAAUUCUAAUGUGGAGUCAGUGCUCAGUGGUUCAGCUAGCAUGGCUCAAAAUCUGCAUGAUGAGUCCCUCUCCACAAGCCCUCAUGGGGCUCUCCACCAGCACGUGACUGAUAUUCAGCUUCAUAUUCUUAAAAAUAGGAUGUAUGGAUGUGAUUCUGUAAAGCAACCAAGAAAUAUAGAGGAACCCAGCAACAUACCUGUAUCAGAGAAGGAUUCUAAUUCUCAGGUGGAUUUAAGCAUUCGGGUUACUGAUGAUGAUAUUGGUGAAAUAAUUCAAGUAGAUGGAAGCGGUGAUACAUCUUCCAAUGAAGAAAUAGGAAGUACAAGAGAUGCAGAUGAGAAUGAAUUUCUAGGGAAUAUUGACGGGGGAGAUCUGAAGGUACCUGAAGAAGAAGCUGACAGUAUUUCAAAUGAGGAUUCAGCCACAAACAGUAGUGAUAAUGAAGACCCUCAAGUAAACAUUGUAGAAGAGGACCCUUUAAAUUCUGGAGAUGAUGUUAGUGAACAGGAUGUGCCAGACCUGUUUGACACGGAUAAUGUUAUUGUCUGUCAGUAUGAUAAGAUUCAUCGAAGCAAGAACAAAUGGAAAUUCUAUUUGAAAGAUGGUGUUAUGUGUUUUGGAGGGAGAGACUAUGUAUUUGCAAAAGCCAUUGGUGAUGCAGAGUGGUAAACCUUGUGAGCUCAGUACAUCUAUUUUGUGAACAUCAGUUGGAUUAUAUUGCAUAUUGUGAAUUCAUUUUUAUUUUGAAUAUAGUCCAGCACAGAGCUGUUCAAAUUUUUAGUUCACUGUAUGGAAUUUAAUAAAAUUAUAAUUCAGAUGCAGAUACAAUUA